CUUUCUUUCCGCGCCGAUAGCGCUCACGCAAGCAUGGUUAACGUCCCUAAAACCCGCCGGACUUUCUGUAAGAAGUGUGGCAAGCACCAACCCCAUAAAGUGACACAGUACAAGAAGGGCAAGGAUUCUCUGUACGCCCAGGGAAAGCGGCGUUAUGACAGGAAGCAGAGUGGCUAUGGUGGGCAAACUAAGCCGAUUUUCCGGAAAAAGGCUAAAACUACAAAGAAGAUUGUGCUAAGGCUUGAGUGCGUUGAGCCCAACUGCAGAUCUAAGAGAAUGCUGGCUAUUAAAAGAUGCAAGCAUUUUGAACUGGGAGGAGAUAAGAAGAGAAAGGGCCAAGUGAUCCAGUUCUAAGUGUCAUCUUUUAUUAUGAAGACAAUAAAAUCUUGAGUUUAUGUUCACUUCAUUUGUUUGCUGUUCAUCUUUUGGGAGGGAAUAAGCUAGAGCCAUCAAUACAAUUCCGCUUGUGGGGAAAUUUAUGCCUCUUACUGGUACUACUUGUUUUGCAUUGAAGCUGACUGGUUGAGUUCACAUCAUAUGUUGCAAUUUUCUAAUUUGGCACUUCAAUCACUAGGGGCCUUAUGAGGCAGUUUGUCAUUAUGCAAUGGUUAUUGGUUAUCAUGUGAGUAGACACAUUUCAGGCUAAUAGGGAGAAGUCAGUAACACAUUCAUAGUGAAUAUGAGAUGUCUUUGCUAAGAGUUAAGUGUCAGAUCUUUGUUAUAACAGUUAAUUUAAUAAAGAAUUUUGGCAUUGUUCUUCA